GUUAGUGCUUCCGGGUUGCAGCCAGGGAAGCCUCCGCGGUGGUGCAAGUGGAACCCAAGCCUUGAGGUUUCAGUGAGUAGGGGGCCGACGUGAGCUUUAGCGUCCCCCUUUAGCCUCCCUCUUCGAUUCCUUGAAGACCCUGGUGCAGCUUAGCAAGAGGGCCCAGGAUUUUUGGAUCCCCAGCCCUGUGACAAGGGUUCCUGUCCAGUUUCCCCCUCCCAGGAUUUCGACUCAGUUCAGCGAAGUCACCGCCCCGUCUGAGAAAUGAGGACACCAAGGCUUAGAGCACAGCCCCGAGGCGCCGUCUACCAGGCCCCGUCCCCUCCCCCGGCUCCUGUCGGUCAGCACUGAAACCCCGUCCCUGCUCCAGGCCUCCUUCUCUGGGGUCCAAGGUCCCAUACAGGCCUCUGCCUCGGCCGCAGGCCCUUCAGUCACCGUCGCCUCGUCUCCCUGACUGUCCGCAGGCCUGGGCAGCAUGGCCGUAUUCCGGUCGGGUCUCCUGGUGCUGACGACGCCGCUGGCCUCCCUAGCCCCUCGCCUGGCCUCCAUCCUGACCUCGGCGGCCCGGCUGGUGAAUCACACACUCUAUGUUCACCUGCAGCCGGGCAUGAGCCUGGAGGGCCCGGCUCAGCCCCAGUCCAGCCCCGUGCAGGCCACGUUUGAGGUUCUUGAUUUCAUCACGCACCUCUAUGCUGGCGCCGACGUCCACAGGCACUUGGACGUCAGAAUCCUACUGACCAAUAUCCGAACCAAGAGCACCUUUCUCCCUCCCCUGCCCACCUCAGUCCAGAAUCUCGCCCACCCGCCAGAAGUCGUGUUGACAGAUUUCCAGACCCUGGAUGGAAGCCAGUACAACCCGGUCAAACAGCAGCUAGUGCGUUACGCCACCAGCUGUUACAGCUGUUGUCCGCGACUGGCCUCGGUGCUGCUAUACUCCGAUUAUGGGAUAGGAGAAGUGCCCGUGGAGCCCCUGGAUGUCCCCUUACCCUCCACGAUCAGGCCAGCUUCCCCCGUGGCCGGGUCUCCAAAGCAGCCGGUGCGUGGCUACUACCGUGGCGCUGUCGGUGGCACGUUUGACCGCCUGCACAACGCCCACAAGGUGUUGCUCAGUGUCGCGUGCAUCCUGGCCCAGGAGCAGCUUGUGGUGGGAGUAGCAGACAAAGAUCUGUUGAAGAGCAAGUUGCUCCCUGAGCUGCUCCAACCUUAUACAGAACGUGUGGAACAUCUGAGUGAAUUCCUGGUGGACAUCAAGCCCUCCUUGACUUUUGAUGUCAUCCCCCUGCUGGACCCCUAUGGGCCCGCUGGCUCUGACCCCUCCCUGGAGUUCCUGGUGGUCAGCGAGGAGACCUAUCGUGGGGGGAUGGCCAUCAACCGCUUCCGCCUUGAGAAUGACCUGGAGGAACUUGCUUUGUACCAGAUCCAGCUGCUGAAGGACCUCAGACAUACAGAGAAUGAAGAGGACAAAGUCAGCUCCUCCAGCUUCCGCCAGCGAAUGUUGGGGAACCUGCUUCGGCCUCCAUAUGAAAGGCCAGAGCUCCCCACAUGUCUCUAUGUAAUUGGGCUGACUGGCAUCAGUGGCUCUGGGAAGAGCUCAAUAGCUCAGCGACUGAAGGGCCUGGGGGCGUUUGUCAUUGACAGUGACCACCUGGGUCAUCGGGCCUAUGCCCCAGGUGGCCCUGCCUACCAGCCUGUGGUGGAGGCCUUUGGAACAGAUAUUCUCCAUAAAGAUGGCAUCAUCAACAGGAAGGUCCUAGGCAGCCGGGUGUUUGGGAAUAAGAAGCAGCUGAAGAUACUCACGGACAUUAUGUGGCCAAUUAUCGCAAAGCUGGCCCGAGAGGAGAUGGAUCGGGCUGUGGCUGAGGGAAAGCGUGUGUGUGUGAUUGAUGCCGCUGUGUUGCUUGAAGCCGGCUGGCAGAACCUGGUCCAUGAGGUGUGGACUGCUGUCAUCCCAGAGACUGAGGCUGUAAGACGCAUUGUGGAGAGGGAUGGCCUCAGUGAAGCCGCGGCUCAAAGCCGGCUGCAGAGCCAGAUGAGCGGGCAGCAGCUUGUGGAACAGAGCCACGUGGUGCUCAGCACCUUGUGGGAGCCGCAUAUCACCCAACGCCAGGUGGAGAAAGCCUGGGCCCUCUUGCAGAAGCGCAUUCCCAAGACUCAUCAGGCCCUCGACUGAAAAGUUCUCAGUGGGGCCAGACUGGCUCCUGGAGCUGACAAGCGACCCCGUGGUGAGGAGAAAUGGGGGCCUUGAUGCUCACCCUGGUUCAGGCCCAGAGGUCCAAGCUAUACUGUGCAGGACAUGGCCAGGCCUGGUGGACACAGGAAGCCUACCCAACACGCUGGUAUUUGGCCAACACUGAGGAUGUGGUUCAUGGGGGAGCAGUCCCCUCCCCACUCUUGCCCAUGGGUGACUCUUACCCACAGCUGACUAGGGCCAGCGCAAAUACUGGAACCUGUAACAGAAUUAAAGGUGAAUGUUCUGAGA